GGCCAGAAACGGCAGUGGCAGCAGCGUCCGGAGCAGCCGCAGCCUUCUGGAAGCUCCAGGCGGUCUUUCUGCCGAGCCUCGGUCCCGGCCCCCAUCCUCCCCGCCCCAUCGGUUGUUGUCUGGGCGGGUGAGUGUCUCCCCCUCUCCCACCAGCGUUUGCUGGCUCACCCUCCCCUCGCCCCAGUUUUUCCUGGGGGCUCCUCAGGCUCUCGGGGACUGCGGCGGCUGCGGCAGAACAGGGCUGUUUCUCGGGCUUGGCGUUUCCUCGGCCGGGCUGGCGAUUCUGCACCGGGAGAAGCUCCGCUGCUGCCGAGCCCGCGUCCCCCGCGAAGAGCCUGCAAUUGGGUAUUCUCUGCAGGAUGUCAGAGUCGGGGCUUUGCAGGCAAGGGCAAGAUUUAAACAGUCAAGUAAAAUCAAGCUGGGUAAUCAUGGCAGAAGGUGGAUUUGAUCCCUGUGAAUGUGUUUGCUCUCAUGAACAUGCAAUGAGAAGACUGAUCAAUCUGUUACGGCAGUCCCAGUCCUACUGCACAGACACAGAGUGUCUUCAGGAAUUACCGGGACCCUCUGGUGAUAAUGGCAUCAGUGUUACAAUGAUCUUGGUAGCCUGGAUGGUUAUUGCAUUGAUCUUGUUCUUACUGAGACCUCCUAAUCUAAGAGGAUCCAGCCUACCUGGAAAGCCAACCAGUCCUCAUAAUGGACAAGAUCCACCAGCUCCUCCUGUGGACUAACUUUGUGAUAUGGGAAGUGAAAAUAGUUAACACCUUGCACGACCAAACGAACGAAGAUGACCAGAGUACUCUUAACCCCAUUAGAACUGUUUUUCCUUUUGUAUCUGCAAUAUGGGAUGGUAUUGUUUUCAUGAGCUUCUAGAAAUUUCACUUGCAAGUUUAUUUUUGCUUCCUGUGUUACUGCCAUUCCUAUUUACAGUAUAUUUGAGUGAAUGAUUAUAUUUUUAAAAAGUUACAUGGGGCUUUUUUGGUUGUCCUAAACUUACAAACAUUCCACUCAUUCUGUUUGUAACUGUGAUUAUAAUUUUUGUGAUAAUUUCUGGCCUGAUUGAAGGAAAUUUGAGAGGUCUGCAUUUAUAUAUUUUAAAUAGAUUUGAUAGGUUUUUAAAUUGCUUUUUUUCAUAAGGUAUUUAUAAAGUUAUUUGGGGUUGUCUGGGAUUGUGUGAAAGAAAAUUAGAACCACGCUGUAUUUACAUUUACCUUGGUAGUUUAUUUGUGGAUGGCAGUUUUCUGUAGUUUUGGGGACUGUGGUAGCUCUUGGAUUGUUUUGCAAAUUACAGCUGAAAUCUGUGUCAUGGAUUAAACUGGCUUAUGUGGCUAGAAUAGGAAGAGAGAAAAAAUGAAAUGGUUGUUUACUAAUUUUAUACUCCCAUUAAAAAUCUCUAAUGUUAAGAAAACCUUAAAUAAACAUGAUUGAUCAAUAUGGCAGAUGAUUUACAGUCCAUUAUAUGACAUUUGUAAGCCACUCAACACUAGCCUUACAAGGUUCAUGAAAGGAGGAAAACAUUAAUUCUUUCUGCCUUUGCUGAUAUAAUCCACAUAGUAAUAAUUUAAGCUAUAAUUUAUUUUUAAAAUGAGUGCCUCUUGGGAAGCUUCUUUUCUGUUCUAACAGUUCCCUGUUAAAAUGAAAAUCUUAGGCCAGUGCAGUGGCUCACACCUGUAAUCCCAGCACUUUGGGAGGCUGAGGUGGGUGGAUCACUUGAGGUCAGGAGUUCGAGACCAGCCUGGCCAACAUGGUGAAACCCUGUCUCUACUAAAAAUACAGAAAAAUUAGCCAGGGUUGGUGCAUGUGCCUGUAAUCCCAGCUACUCAGGAGGCCAAAGCAGGAGAAUUGCUUGAACCCGGGAGGUGGAGGUUGCAGUGAACCAAGAUCGCACCACUGCAUUCCAGCCUAAGCAAUAGAGCGAGACUCCCUCUCAAAAAAAAAAAAAGAAGAAAAUCUUAAAGCUGUAUUAGGGCCUGUUAGGUUACUGAUAUUUGAAUGCCUAUUUACUUAUUUACUACAUUGAGUCUUUUGUUAUCCUCUGACCUAUAAAAUAUUUUAAUAAAUUACUGGUUUACUUCAAGGGAAAAGAAGGAAAAUGAGAAACAUACAUCUUUUUUUCACUCCUUAUCUCAUUCCUGUUUGGUGAUGGGAUGGAUUGGGGUAGGAAGGAAUGUUAAUAUGAGAGAAAUUUUAAAAUGUAUAAAAAAGUAAAAGGUUGUAUUGUUUUGCUCAGUUUGAAAUAAAGUGAAUACCAAUAGCACUUAAAAAUGUCUGCAUGGGCUGGGCACGGUGGCUCACGCCUGUAAUCCCAGCACUUUGGGAGGCCGAGGCAGGCGAAUCACCUGAGGUCAGGAGUUCGAGACCAGCCUGACCAACAUGGUGAAACCUUAUCUCUACUAAAAAUGCAAAAAUUAGCCAGGCAUGGUGGUGUGUGCCUAUAAUCCCAGCUACUGGGGAAGCUGAGGCAGGAAAUUGCUUGAACCUGGGAGACGGAGGUUGCAGUAAGCUGAGAUCGUGCCACUGCACUCCAAUCAGGGCGACAGAGCGAGACUCUGUCUCAAAAUAAAUAAAUAAAUAAAAAUGUCUGCAUGACCCAUAUGGUUAUGAAGUUUUUUUCCUAGCAAAUGAUUGCAGAUUAUUUAUGGGGGCUAGAAGAUAUUUUGCUAUCAAUGUAAGGAUUUUUUUCCCCUUAGGUCAGUCUAUUCACUGUUUAGAUCUGGUAAAUUACUUGUAUGAAUUGAAUAAAUUCUCUGUAUCAUUGUACUGUUUAAUAGUCUCUGAUACAAUUGUGAUACUCAUAAGGUAUUUUCCCCCCUUUAUUAUGAUUACAUUCUAGAUCAUAAACAUUGUAAGGGCAUCUUUUCAUUAUAUAAUCCAAUAUUGAUUGUUUGAAUUCCUCCUUGUACAUCCUGGCUUUGUGCUCAAUUUCUUGAAAUAAUAUAACCAACUCUAAAUUACUUGUGUUAAUAGAUCGGUAACAUGACACAGGUAAGUUAAAUCCUGGAUAAAUGAGCCCCACAGAAUAAAGGUUUUUCCUCUUGCUGUGGCCUACUGGAAGCCUUCCUAACUCUAUAGCUGGUAAAGUAGAGCAGAAAGGGCCAGAAUGGCUUAAGAUGGAGCUAAAUCCCUAUAGCAUUCCAUUUUCUGCUCUUGCCUCUUGAACUUAGAAGGCUUGCCCAUAUAUCCUAACAAUCUGUUCUCUGAGCUGUUAGGCCAAUCCCUGGCAAGAGAUAUUGAUGUAGUCACUGAAUCUAUGGCUCACAAAUAAUUGAAAAUUGGCUUUGGGAGCUGGGCGCAGUGACUCAUGCCUGUAAUCCCAGCACUUUGGGAGGCUGGGGCAGGUGGAUCACUUGAGGUCAGGAGGUUGAGACCAGCCUGGCCAAGACGGUGAAACCCCGUGCCUACAAAAAAUUAGCCGGGUUUGGUGACACGGCCUGUAGUCUUAGCUACUCGGGAGGCUGAGGCAGGAGAAUCGCUUGAGCCUGGGAGACAGGUUGCAGUAAGCCAAGAUCACGCCACUGCACUCCAGCUUGAGUGACAGAGUGAGACCCUGUCUCAAAAAAAAAAGGCUUUAGAAGGCUUUAUUGGAUGAAAUGGCUGAAACUUGGAUACAGAAUGUCUAGUAUUAGACACCUAAAAAUCUGGAUUCUUUUUGGUUGUUGUUUUGAGAUGGAGUUUUGCUCUUUCGCCCAAGCUGGAGUGAAGUGGCGCGACCUUGGCUCACUGCAACAUCCACCCCCAGGUUCGAGCGAUUCUCCUUCCUCAGCCUCCUGAGUAGCUGGGAUUAUAAGUGCCCACCACCACGCCCAGCUAAUUUUUGUAUCUUUAGUAGAGAUGGGGUUUCGCCAUGUAGGCCAGGCUGGUCUCAAACUCCUGACCUCAGGUGAUCCACCCACUAUGGCCUCCCAAAGUGCUAGGAUUACAGAUGUGAGCCACCGUGCCUGGCCAGAAAAUCUGGAUUCUUAUUCCUAGUUCUUCAUUUCUGUCACAUGCACUUAGUUGACAUUACAUCUACAUAUAUUAGCUUUUUCCUACAUGAGCCAUCUAUUUACUUAGUAACCAGUGUUCUUAAUGAAGUAUUUAGUCUUGGGUUUCUUGUAAAAUUUCUCUGCAUUCCUUAGACAGUGUACUAUACAUGAAAUAUUCUUGUUGACCUAGUAAUUUAUAUUAUUCCAUUUAAUUCUUAAACCUAUGGCCUUUUUAUUGAGCACACUCUUAAAUCAUUAUUUGGCUUGUAAACAUUCAUCUGAAGUGUGGCUACAAUCCUCUUUAAAUAAUCUAGGAAAAAAGAAAGAUAAAGCUUACAUUUUCACAGUUUUGGCUCUUAAACACAUUCCACAAAUGCCAUUAAGAAUUUAUUUUGUUUUAGGCCAGUCAUGGUGGCUCAUGCCUGUAAUCCCAGCAAUUUGGGAGGCUGAGGCAAGAACUGCUUGAGCCCAGGAGUUUGAGACUAGCCUGGGCAACAUAGCAAGACCCUGUCUCUACCAAAAAAAAAAAAGUUUAUUUUGUUUUAGAGUCAUUUAAUGUGUUUUUAUGCACAAUAAUAGUGGGAGGUUGUUUUGUUGCAUUUGUUUGUUUGUUUUGUUUUGUUUUGUUUUGCUUUCCAUGUGGGAAAAGUUAACAUUGGAACUGUUUCUAGUAAAAGAUUUUUUUCAGGCUGGGCACGGUGGCUCAUGCCUGUAAUCCCAACACUUUGGGAGACCGAGGGAGCUGGAUCACCUGAGGUCAGGAGUUCGAGACCAGCCUGGCCAACAUGGAAAAACUCCAUCUCCACUAAAAAUACAAAAGUAGCCUGGUGUGGUGGCACAUGCCUGUAAUCCCAGCUACUUGGGAAGCUGAGGCAGGAGAAUCACUUGAACCUGGGAGGUGGAGGUUGCAGUGAGCCAAGAUCACGCCAUUGCACUCCAGCCUGGGCAACAAGAGUGAAACUCCGUCUCAAAAAAAAAAAAAAAAAGAUGUUUUUCAUUUUUUUCAUGUUAUCUAUCCAAGCACUGUUCCAUGGUCAGCAAGUCAUAUUUCAUAAUGUGGAUUUUCCAAAAUAAUUAUUGAAUACAGCUAUUCUAUGGCUACUUUUAGUGUUUUUGUGGUAUGUGGUGUGGGAGUGUUUAUGGAAUUACCAGUAUCUUAAAUUUUCAAAGGAACCUUGGAAGUCUAUCACUCUAAAUGAAAGUCUGUCACUCUACAUGAAUUAUGUGCUCAAAUUUGACCAACUCAGUUUAAGACACAAAACAGUAAUUUGAAGAAGGAAAAAUGAAGAGAGUUUCUAGUUUAAUGGGUUAAAUUUUUGUUGUUGCAAUAGUAAGUUUAGUCUUCUUAUAAUAUUUCUAAAUGAAAAAUCAUAGGUAUUUGUUACCAUGUGUGAAGAUUAGUUUGUUAAAAGCAAAAGUGGUCGUGUGAUAUGCUAAAUGUUAAUUACUGAUUUUAUAUGUUUAAAUCACGCCAAACAAAUUAUGUCUGUGCCAUCCAGGGUCUGUUGUUAAUCUUUUUCUGAGUACUUGGAUUGGGAUAAAGGGCUUGUACUAUGCACUUUUUAUUAAUGAAUAAAUAGAAAACGUUAGUAACACUUUGUGUUUUCUGUUUGGCUUUUGUGGGAAGAGAAGCAAGCAUCUUUUGCCUAGUAGAUGUUAACAUUGUGUAUUAAACAGUUUCUUUGUAAGACCUAACUAAAGACAUUCCUAAGAGAGAACUUAAGUUUUAAGAAAAGUUGUGAGAAAAAUAUUCAUAAAAUAUGCAGUAUGGGGCCAGUAUUCAGAAGUAGAGUUUCUCUCUUGGAAAUUAGAUUGCAGUCACAUUUCUUUGGUUAUUUUCUUUCUCUCUCUCUUCCUAGAAUACCAGGUAAAAUAGACAUUUACUUUGAGGGACUAAUAUCCAAUAGUGUUAAUUAUUUAAGCAGAUAUAUCUAGCUCAAAAGGAACCAGACAUGUCACUGUACCAAAAACACACAAAAGUGAAAAUUUGCUUCUGUUCUGUGACCUAGAAUGUGUCCAGACAUUAAAGGUCAUGAAUACUCAUAUACAUGUAAAAAUAGUAACACUGCUCUGGCAUGAUUUUGACGUCAGUGUUUAUGUAAUAACUUCAGUGUUAUAUUUAAAAUAGAUAAAUUUGUGAAAUAACAAUUUCUUGGAGACAGUCAACUUUUUAUGAUUUAAUCUAAAGAUUGUCAUGUACAUGUCAACGGAUAUCUGAAUCCUCAGUGAAACUGUUAAGUUUUCAUUAAAUGACUCUGCUGCAAUACUAGUUUUCUUCUCAGAAAAUGGAAUUCAAAUAAAAUAAGUUUUUUGGUCUUGGCAUUUCACCUGAUGACUUUCUCUGUUCUGGAUCUCAAUUUGUAGAGUUGUUGGGGGUUCCCCCCCCUCCAAAAGAUGCUCCAUAAACACCAACUACAAUUAUCUUUCAUGAUCAUAUUUUUAAAAAUUGGAGUUACCUGUGUGAUCUUUUCCCAUUAGUUGCUUGUAGGGGACUUUAGUGUGCGUAUCUCUUCUCAGACAAAUGUAUUAUGUUCGUUCAAUAAACACUUCAACAAA